AGUUUCCCAAUCAGGUAGUGAGAGUGGCACGAACCAGCCGUUCUCCUGAGCCACCCCCCGCGCCCCCGGACUCCUCAAUAUCCCAGGUGGGAACGCUCACCAGGGACAUCCAGCGCCCGUCGCCCUGUACGUCCUGCACCGGCGUGGGCUUGCUGGCUGGGUUCUCCUCUCCACUCAUCUUGGCGCCGCAGCUCCUGCAGGAUGAGCGAGUCGGGUCGGCCCGGGAGUGUUCCGAACGGAGCUGGCUCCGCCACGCCCACUCCUACCCCUCGCGGCAACAAAGGACCGUCCCAACGCUAGCACACCCGCGGAGGACGAAGGCCGAUACAGGGCGCCGCCUCCUCUCCAGGGACGGAAGCCUUCACUUAGGAGGACACCAUGGAUACCCAGGGACCAGUCUCCCAGCCUUUUCAGCAGCCUGAGAAACCUGGUCGUGUCCGUCGUCGGAAGACUAGGCGGGAACGUAACAAGGCCCUGGUGGGCAGCCGCCGGCCAUUAGCCCACCACGAUCCUCCUGUGGCCAUUCGGGAUCCACCUGUGGUCCCUACUGCCUCCAAGCUCGUGGUCAUAACCCAGGGCCGGCUGAGCCGGGAGCACCGGGGUCUCUUCAACCACGAGGUGAAAUCCCUAGAUGUUGCAAGGCUGCUUAGCAGUGGGACCCUGGUGCCAGGCAGCCCCACACUCCCCGCCAAGCCCUCCCCAAGCCCAGGCAGGGCCCAGGAACCAGCCCCACGGUCCAGGGACAAAGAGAACCAGGUGCCUGGAGGUUCGGGCCCAGGCCCACCCAGUUCCCCAGAGUUGUCUGGCGUGGGGCAGCUGCUGGCAGAGCUGCAGUGUCAGCUGAGUUUGCCACAGGCCUUCCCCCGGAGGAACCUGAUUCAGGAUGCCAGGGAUGCCAUCGUGCACACCUUGCAGGCCUGUCAUGGUUGUGUGCCUGACCUUGCCCUGGUGCUUCGGGGCUGCCAGCCACCCUUGCCAGGGGCCAAGCCUGGGGUCUCUGAGAGAAAGAUGACACCCUUCUGGAUUAAUAGCCCUGAUCAAGUCCCAGAGCAGGAGAGGCAAAGGAAGCAACAAGGGACAAAGGAGUUCACCUUCCCCAUGCCCUACACCUCCAGCAUGCCCACUGCGCACAGGGGGAGUCUGGCACCGCCAAGAGGUCCCUGGCCACCAUACUUUCCCUCACUGUCUUCGCCAUCUGGAACAGCCUGGGGUCCCCCAACAGCGUUUGACUUGUUAAAAAGCAUCUGGCUGGUAGCCACGCCACCCCCUCCUCGGCCCUGGGGGGUUGGCCUCCCUCAGCCCCUGCCUCAGCCUUCAUCACCCCUGUUGCCCCGAACCUCUGUCCUGGACUGGAGCCCCAGCCCCCCUUCCCCACUGCCCAGCCUCUCCUGGGUAGUAGCCCAGAGCAGUCCGGAAGCCUGGUCUUUUCCACCCAUGAGACUGUACUGAGGAGAGGCUGAGGCUAGGGCUGGGGACAGAUAUCUUGUACUCCCAGUGACCUCAAUAAAGUACUUUUCAUGGUC